GCAGGCGCGCCGAGAUGGCCGCGCUCCUGGCCGCCUAGAGCCGGAGCGGCCCGCGGAGCUGCGGAGGCAGCCAUGGUCGGGGCGCUGUGCGGCUGCUGGUUCCGCCUGGGCGGGGCCCGCCCGCUCAUCCCGUUGGGCCCGACUGUGGUACAGACCUCCAUGAGCCGGUCCCAGGUAGCCCUGCUGGGCCUGAGUCUGCUGCUCAUGCUCCUACUGUAUGUGGGGCUGCCAGGCCCCCCUGAGCAGACUUCCUGCCUCUGGGGAGACCCCAAUGUCACAGUCCUGGCUGGUCUCACCCCUGGCAACUCGCCCAUCUUUUACCGCGAGGUGCUCCCACUCAACCAGGCACACAGGGUGGAGGUGGUGCUGCUUCAUGGAAAGGCCUUUAACUCUCACACGUGGGAGCAGCUGGGCACACUGCAGCUACUGUCACAGAGGGGCUACCGGGCCGUGGCCCUUGACCUUCCAGCUCACCACGCGCAGCGCCAUGACCAGCAAGGGUCCCGAGGAGGAGCACCCAUCGGUGACGCUCUUCCGCCAGUACCUGCGUAUCCGCACUGUCCAGCCCAAGCCUGACUAUGGAGCUGCUGUGGCUUUCUUUGAGGAGACAGCCCGCCAGCUGGGCCUGGGCUGUCAGAAAGUAGAGGUGGCACCUGGCUAUGUGGUGACCGUGUUGACCUGGCCAGGCACCAACCCUACACUCUCCUCCAUCUUGCUCAACUCCCACACGGAUGUGGUGCCUGUCUUCAAGGAACAUUGGAGUCACGACCCCUUUGAGGCCUUCAAGGAUUCUGAGGGCUACAUCUAUGCCAGGGGUGCCCAGGACAUGAAGUGCGUCAGCAUCCAGUACCUGGAAGCUGUGAGGAGGCUGAAGGUGGAGGGCCACCGGUUCCCCAGAACCAUCCACAUGACCUUUGUGCCUGAUGAGGAGGUUGGGGGUCACCAAGGCAUGGAGCUGUUCGUGCAGCGGCCUGAGUUCCACGCCCUGAGGGCAGGCUUUGCCCUGGAUGAGGGCAUAGCCAAUCCCACUGAUGCCUUCACUGUCUUUUAUAGUGAGCGGAGUCCCUGGUGGGUGCGGGUUACCAGCACUGGGAGGCCAGGCCAUGCCUCACGCUUCAUGGAGGACACAGCAGCAGAGAAGCUGCACAAGGUUGUAAACUCCAUCCUGGCAUUCCGGGAGAAGGAAUGGCAGAGGCUGCAGUCAAACCCCCACCUGAAAGAGGGGUCCGUGACCUCCGUGAACCUGACUAAGCUAGAGGGUGGCGUGGCCUAUAACGUGAUACCUGCCACCAUGAGCGCCAGCUUUGACUUCCGUGUGGCACCGGAUGUGGACUUCAAGGCUUUUGAGGAGCAGCUGCAGAGCUGGUGCCAGGCAGCUGGCGAGGGGGUCACCCUAGAGUUUGCUCAGAAGUGGAUGCACCCCCAAGUGACACCUACUGAUGACUCAAACCCUUGGUGGGCAGCUUUUAGCCGGGUCUGCAAGGAUAUGAACCUCACUCUGGAGCCUGAGAUCAUGCCUGCUGCCACUGACAACCGCUAUAUCCGCGCGGUGGGGGUCCCAGCUCUAGGCUUCUCACCCAUGAACCGCACACCUGUGCUGCUGCACGACCACGAUGAACGGCUGCAUGAGGCUGUGUUCCUCCGUGGGGUGGACAUAUAUACACGCCUGCUGCCUGCCCUUGCCAGUGUGCCUGCCCUGCCCAGUGACAGCUGAGCCCUGGAACUCCUAAACCUUUGCCCCUGGGGCUUCCAUCCCAACCAGUGCCAAGGACCUCCUCUUCCCCCUUCCAAAUAAUAAAGUCUAUGGACAGGGCUGUCUCUGAAGUACUAACACAA